CCUUCCCAGGGUCCUCACCCUUGGGCCUCUUGGGGACUACCGAUGAGCCUCCUCCCUCAGGCCCCUCGACGACGCAAGGGGCCCAGGCUCCUCUCCUGCAGCAGCGCCCCCAGGAGCUGGGAGAGUUGAGGGUGCUGGGCAGAGAUGAGACAGGGCGCCUCCGUGUGGUCUGGACCGCCCAGCCUGACACCUUUGCCUACUUCCAACUGCGCAUGCGGGUGCCCGAGGGGCCGGGGGCACAUGAGGAAGUGCUGCCAGGGGACGUCCGCCAGGCUCUGGUGCCUCCACCCCCUCCUGGAACCCCGUAUGAGCUGUCACUUCAUGGGGUCCCUCCUGGGGGCAAGCCCUCUGACCCCAUCAUCUACCAAGGCAUUAUGGACAAGGAUGAGGAGAAGCCUGGGAAGUCCUCAGGCCCACCACGCCUGGGUGAGCUGACGGUGACAGACAGGACCUCCGACUCCUUGCUCCUGCGCUGGACGGUCCCCGAGGGCGAGUUUGACUCCUUCGUGAUCCAGUACAAAGACAGGGACGGGCAGCCCCAGGUGGUGCCCGUGGAAGGACCCCAGCGCUCGGCCGUCAUCACCUCCCUGGAUCCUGGCCGCAAGUACAAAUUUGUCCUGUAUGGGUUUGUUGGCAAGAAGAGGCAUGGUCCGCUGGUGGCUGAAGCCAAGAUCUUGCCUCAGAGUGACCCAAGUCCAGGGACUCCACCCCACCUGGGAAACCUGUGGGUGACAGACCCUACCCCAGAUUCACUGCACCUCUCCUGGACUGUCCCUGAGGGCCAGUUUGACACCUUCAUGGUCCAGUACAGGGACAGGGAUGGACGGCCCCAGGUGGUACCUGUGGAAGGGCCCGAGCGUUCAUUUGUUGUCUCCUCACUGGACCCUGACCACAAGUACAGAUUCACUCUGUUUGGAAUUGCGAACAAGAAGCGGUAUGGCCCCCUCACGGCCGAUGGCACCACUGCUCCAGAGAGGAAAGAGGAGCCCCCCCGCCCUGAGUUCCUGGAGCAGCCCCUCCUGGGGGAACUGACAGUGACCGGCGUGACCCCAGACUCCUUGCGUCUCUCAUGGACAGUGGCCCAGGGCCCCUUCGACUCAUUCAUGGUCCAGUACAAGGAUGCACAGGGGCAGCCCCAGGCAGUGCCUGUUGCGGGGGAUGAGAAUGAGGUUACUGUCCCCGGCCUGGAUCCCGACCGGAAGUAUAAGAUGAACCUCUACGGGCUUCGUGGCAGGCAGCGUGUGGGGCCCGAGUCUGUGGUGGCCAAGACUGCUCCUCAGGAGGAUGUGGACGAGACCCCCAGCCCCACAGAACUGGGCACGGAGGCCCCGGAGUCCCCCGAGGAGCCGCUCCUGGGGGAGCUGACAGUGACAGGAUCCUCCCCUGAUUCGCUGAGCCUCUUCUGGACCGUCCCCCAGGGCAGCUUCGACUCUUUCACCGUGCAGUACAAGGACAGGGAUGGGCGGCCCCAGGCGGUGCGUGUUGGGGGCAAGGAGAGUGAGGUCACCGUGGGAGGCCUAGAGCCCGGGCACAAGUACAAGAUGCACCUGUACGGCCUCCACGAGGGGCAGCGCGUGGGCCCGGUGUCCGCCGUGGGCGUGACAGCCCCACAACAAGAAGAGACCCCUCCAGCCACUGAGUCCCCGCUGGAGCCACGCCUAGGAGAGCUGACAGUGACAGAUGUGACCCCCAACUCUGUGGGCCUCUCCUGGACAGUCCCCGAGGGCCAGUUUGACUCCUUCAUAGUCCAGUACAAGGACAAGGACGGGCAGCCCCAGGUGGUGCCGGUGGCGGCAGACCAGCGAGAGGUCACAGUCUACAACCUGGAGCCUGAGAGAAAAUAUAAGAUGAACAUGUAUGGACUACAUGAUGGGCAACGCAUGGGCCCCCUGUCUGUGGUCAUCGUGACGGCUCCCCUCCCACCAGCCCCAGCCACAGAGGCCUCCAAGCCUCCCCUGGAGCCACGCCUAGGGGAGCUGACAGUGACGGAUAUAACCCCUGACUCUGUGGGCCUCUCAUGGACAGUCCCUGAGGGUGAAUUCGACUCCUUUGUGGUUCAGUACAAGGACAGGGACGGGCAGCCCCAGGUGGUGCCCGUGGCUGCAGAUCAGCGGGAGGUCACUAUCCCUGACCUGGAACCCUCCCGCAAGUACAAGUUCCUGCUCUUUGGGAUCCAGGAUGGGAAACGACGCAGCCCAGUCUCUGUGGAGGCAAAGACGGUUGCCCGAGGUGACGCCAGCCCAGGGGCCCCACCCCGCCUUGGGGAGCUGUGGGUGACAGACCCCACCCCAGACUCACUGCGCCUCUCCUGGACGGUUCCUGAGGGCCAGUUCGACUCUUUUGUGGUCCAGUUCAAGGACAAAGACGGGCCCCAGGUGGUGCCCGUGGAGGGCCAUGAGCGCUCUGUCACUGUCACCCCUCUGGAUGCCGGCCGCAAGUACAGAUUCCUCCUCUAUGGCCUCCUGGGCAAGAAGCGCCAUGGCCCUCUCACUGCCGACGGCACCACGGAAGCCCGGAGUGCUAUGGAUGAUACUGGAACAAAGCGUCCCCCAAAACCCCGUCUGGGGGAGGAGCUGCAGGUGACCACCGUGACCCAGAACUCCGUGGGCCUCUCCUGGACAGUCCCUGAGGGCCAGUUUGACUCCUUUGUGGUCCAGUACAAAGACAGGGACGGGCAGCCCCAGGUGGUGCCCGUGGAGGGCAGCCUCAGGGAGGUCAGCGUGCCGGGCCUGGACCCUGCCCACAGGUACAAGCUGCUGCUCUACGGGCUGCACCACGGCAAGCGUGUGGGCCCCAUCUCGGCCGUCGCCAUUACUGCCGGCAGGGAAGAAACGGAAACUGAGACCACGGCCCCGACCCCUCCAGCGCCUGAGCCCCACCUCGGGGAGUUGACAGUGGAGGAGGCCACGUCACACACCCUGCAUCUCUCCUGGAUGGUGACUGAGGGAGAAUUUGACUCCUUCGAAAUCCAGUACACAGAUAGAGACGGGCAACUCCAAAUGGUCCGCAUAGGAGGUGACCGGAAUGACAUCACCCUCUCUGGCCUGGAAUCCGACCACAGAUACCUGGUGACCCUGUAUGGUUUCAGUGAUGGGAAGCAUGUAGGUCCUGUCCAUGUCGAGGCCCUGACAGUCCCGGAGGAGGAGAAGCCUUCAGAACCUCCCACCGCAACCCCCGAGCCCCCCAUCAAGCCUCGCCUGGGGGAGCUGACCGUGACAGAUGCCACCCCUGACUCCCUCAGCCUGUCCUGGACAGUUCCCGAGGGACAGUUUGACCACUUCCUGGUCCAGUACAGGAAUGGAGAUGGGCAGCCCAAGGCAGUGAGGGUGCCAGGGCACGAGGAAGGGGUCACCAUCUCGGGCCUGGAGCCAGACCAUAAAUACAAGAUGAACCUGUACGGCUUCCACGGUGGCCAGCGCAUGGGCCCUGUGUCUGUCGUCGGGGUGACAGCUGCAGAGGAAGAGACCCCCAGCCCCACAGAACCCAGCAUGGAGGCCCCGGAGCCCGCUGAGGAGCCGCUCCUGGGGGAGCUAACAGUGACAGGAUCCUCCCCUGACUCGCUGAGCCUCUCCUGGACCGUCCCCCAGGGCCGCUUCGACUCCUUCACCGUGCAGUACAAGGACAGGGACGGGCGGCCCCAGGUGGUGCGUGUUGGGGGCGAGGAGAGUGAAGUCACCGUGGGGGGCCUGGAGCCUGGGCGCAAGUACAAGAUGCACCUGUACGGCCUCCACGAGGGGCGGCGCGUGGGCCCAGUGUCUGCUGUGGGCGUCACGGCCCCCGAAGAGGAGUCCCCUGAUGCUCCUCUUGCAAAGCUGCGCCUAGGGCAGAUGACAGUGAGAGACAUCACCUCCGACUCCCUCAGCCUCUCCUGGACAGUCCCCGAGGGCCAGUUUGACCAUUUCUUGGUCCAGUUUAAGAAUGGGGACGGGCAGCCCAAGGCGGUGCGGGUGCCGGGACACGAGGAUGGGGUCACCAUCUCGGGCCUGGAGCCAGACCACAAGUACAAGAUGAACCUGUACGGCUUCCACGGUGGCCAGCGCGUGGGCCCCGUGUCUGCUGUUGGUUUAACUGCCCCAGGAAAGGAUGAAGAAAUGGCCCCAGCCUCGACAGAACCUCCCACCCCUGAACCCCCCAUCAAGCCUCGCCUGGAGGAGCUGACCGUGACAGAUGCGACCCCUGACUCCCUCAGCCUGUCCUGGACGGUUCCCGAGGGACAGUUUGACCACUUCCUGGUCCAGUACAAGAAUGGGGAUGGGCAGCCCAAGGCAACACGGGUGCCAGGACAUGAGGACAGGGUCACCAUCUCCGGCCUGGAGCCAGACAACAAGUACAAGAUGAACCUGUACGGCUUCCACGGUGGCCAGCGUGUGGGCCCCGUGUCUGCCAUCGGGGUGACAGCUGCAGAGGAAGAGACCCCCAGCCCCACAGAACCCAGCAUGGAGGCCCCGGAGCCCCCUGAGGAGCCGCUCCUGGGGGAGCUAACAGUGACAGGAUCCUCCCCUGACUCGCUGAGCCUCUCCUGGACCGUCCCCCAGGGCCGCUUCGACUCCUUCACCGUGCAGUACAAGGACAGGGACGGGCGGCCCCAGGUGGUGCGUGUUGGGGGCGAGGAGAGCGAGGUCACCGUGGGGGGCCUGGAGCCUGGGCGCAAAUACAAGAUGCACCUGUAUGGCCUCCACGAGGGGCGGCGCGUGGGCCCGGUGUCCACCGUGGGCGUGACUGCCCCACAAGAGGAUGUGGACGAGACCCCCAGCCCUACAGAACCAGGCACAGAGGCCCCAGGGCCCCCCGAGGAGCCUCUCCUGGGGGAGCUGACAGUGACAGGAUCCUCCCCUGACUCGCUGAGCCUUUCCUGGACCGUCCCCCAGGGCCGCUUUGACUCCUUCACCGUGCAGUACAAGGACAGGGACGGGCGGCCCCAGGCGGUGCGUGUUGGGGGCCAGGAGAGCAAGGUCACUGUGAGGGGCCUGGAGCCUGGGCGCAAGUACAAGAUGCACCUGUACGGCCUCCACGAGGGGCGGCGCCUGGGCCCGGUGUCUGCCGUGGGCGUCACAGAGGAUGAAGCCGAGACCACCCAAGCAGUGCCUACCAUGACCCCUGAGCCCCCCAUCAAGCCUCGCCUGGGGGAGCUGACCAUGACAGAUGCCACCCCUGACUCCCUCAGCCUGUCCUGGACGGUUCCCGAGGGCCAGUUUGACCACUUCCUGGUCCAGUACAGGAAUGGGGAUGGGCAGCCCAAGGCGGUGCGGGUGCCGGGGCACGAGGACGGGGUCACCAUCUCAGGCCUGGAGCCAGACCAUAAAUACAAGAUGAACCUGUACGGCUUCCACGGUGGCCAGCGCGUGGGCCCCAUCUCUGUCAUUGGGGUGACGGCUGCAGAGGAAGAGACCCCCAGCCCCACGGAACUCAGCACUGAGGCCCCGGAGCCCCCUGAGGAGCCGCUCCUGGGGGAGCUGACAGUGACAGGAUCCUCCCCUGACUCGCUGAGCCUCUCCUGGACCAUCCCCCAGGGCCACUUCGACUCCUUCACCGUGCAGUACAAGGACAGGGACGGGCGGCCCCAGGUGAUGCGUGUCAGGGGCGAGGAGAGCGAGGUCACCGUGGGGGGCCUGGAGCCCGGGCGCAAAUACAAGAUGCACCUGUACGGCCUCCACGAGGGGCGGCGUGUGGGCCCGGUGUCCACCGUGGGUGUGACAGCUCCAGAGGAUGAAGCAGAGACCACCCAAGCAGUGCCCACCACAACCCCUGAGCCCCCCAACAAGCCUCGCCUCGGGGAGCUGACCGUGACAGAUGCCACCCCUGACUCCCUCAGCCUGUCCUGGAUGGUCCCCGAGGGCCAGUUUGACCACUUCCUGGUCCAGUACAGGAAUGGGGAUGGGCAGCCCAAGGUGGUGCGGGUGCCGGGGCACGAGGACGGGGUCACCAUCUCAGGCCUGGAGCCAGACCACAAGUACAAGAUGAACCUGUACGGCUUCCACGGUGGCCAGCGCGUGGGCCCCAUCUCUGUCAUUGGGGUGACAGCUGCAGAGGAAGAAACUCCCGCCCCCACAGAACCCAGCACGGAGGCCCCGGAGCCCCCUGAGGAGCCGCUCCUGGGGGAGCUGACAGUGACAGGAUCCUCCCCUGACUCGCUGAGCCUCUCCUGGACCAUCCCCCAGGGCCGCUUCGACUCCUUCACUGUGCAGUACAAGGACAGGGACGGGCGGCCCCAGGUGGUGCGUGUCAGGGGCGAGGAGAGCGAGGUCACCGUGGGGGGCCUGGAGCCCGGGUGCAAAUACAAGAUGCACCUGUACGGCCUCCACGAGGGGCAGCGCGUGGGCCCAGUGUCCGCUGUGGGUGUGACAGCUCCAAAGGAUGAAGCCGAGACCACCCAAGCAGUGCCUACCAUGACCCCUGAGCCCCCCAUCAAGCCUCGCCUGGGGGAGCUGACCGUGACAGAUGCCACCCCCGACUCCCUCAGCCUGUCCUGGAUGGUUCCCGAGGGCCAGUUUGACCACUUCCUGGUCCAGUACAGGAAUGGGGAUGGGCAGCCCAAGGCGGUGCGGGUGCCGGGGCACGAGGACGGGGUCACCAUCUCAGGCCUGGAGCCAGACCAUAAAUACAAGAUGAACCUGUACGGCUUCCACGGUGGCCAGCGCGUAGGCCCUGUGUCUGCCAUUGGGGUGACGGAGGAAGAGACCCCCAGCCCCACAGAACCCAGCACUGAGGCCCCGGAGGCCCCUGAGGAGCCGCUCCUGGGGGAGUUGACAGUGACAGGAUCCUCCCCUGACUCGCUGAGCCUCUCCUGGACCGUCCCCCAGGGCCGCUUCGACUCCUUCACCGUGCAGUACAAGGACAGGGACGGGCAGCCCCAGGUGGUGCGUGUCAGGGUCGAGGAGAGCGAGGUCACCGUGGGGGGCCUGGAGCCCGGGCGCAAAUACAAGAUGCAUCUGUACGGCCUCCACGAGGGGCAGCGCGUGGGCCCAGUGUCCACCGUGGGCAUCACGGCGCCCCUGCCCACACCACUGCCGGUGGAGCCCCGCCUGGGGGAGCUGGCGGUGGCGGCCGUGACCUCGGACUCAGUGGGCCUCUCAUGGACGGUGGCCCAGGGCCCCUUUGACUCCUUCCUGGUACAGUACAGGGACGCGCAGGGGCAGCCCCAGGCAGUGCCUGUGAGCGGAGACCUCCGAGCGGUCGCCGUCUCGGGGCUGGACCCGGCCCGCAAGUACAAGUUCCUGCUCUUUGGACUCCAGAAUGGGAAACGCCACGGCCCAGUCCCUGUGGAGGCCAGGACCGCCCCAGACACCAAACCGUCUCCCCGCCUGGGGGAGCUGACUGUGACAGAUGCGACCCCUGACUCCGUGGGCCUCUCGUGGACGGUCCCUGAGGGCGAAUUCGACUCCUUCGUGGUCCAGUACAAGGAUAAGGAUGGUCGGCUCCAGGUGGUGCCGGUGGCAGCCAACCAGCGGGAGGUCACAGUCCAGGGCCUGGAGCCCAGUAGGAAAUACAGGUUCCUGCUCUAUGGUCUGUCAGGCAGGAAACGACUGGGCCCCAUCUCUGCUGACAGCACCACAGCUCCCCUGGAGAAGGAGCUACCUCCCCACCUGGGGGAACUGACCGUGGCUGAGGAGACCUCCAGCUCUCUGCGCCUGUCCUGGACGGUAGCCCAGGGCCCCUUUGACUCCUUCGUGGUCCAGUACAGGGACACGGACGGGCAGCCCAGGGCAGUGCCUGUGGCCGCAGACCAGCGCACAGUCACCGUAGAGGACCUGGAGCCUGGCAAGAAAUACAAGUUUCUGCUCUACGGGCUCCUUGGGGGAAAGCGCCUGGGCCCGGUCUCUGCCCUGGGAAUGACAGCCCCAGAAGAGGACACACCAGCCCCAGAGUUAGCCCCAGAGGCCCCUGAGCCUCCUGAAGAGCCCCGCCUAGGAGUGCUGACCGUGACCGACACAACCCCAGACUCCAUGCGCCUCUCGUGGAGCGUGGCCCAGGGCCCCUUUGAUUCCUUCGUGGUCCAGUAUGAGGACACGAACGGGCAGCCCCAGGCCUUGCUCGUGGACGGCGACCAGAGCAAGAUCCUCAUCUCAGGCCUGGAGCCCAGCACCCCCUACAGGUUCCUCCUCUAUGGCCUCCAUGAAGGGAAGCGCCUGGGGCCCCUCUCAGCUGAGGGCACCACAGGGCUGGCUCCUGCUGGUCAGACCUCAGAGGAGUCAAGGCCCCGCCUGUCCCAGCUGUCUGUGACUGACGUGACCACCAGUUCACUGAGGCUCAACUGGGAGGCCCCACCGGGGGCCUUCGACUCCUUCCUGCUCCGCUUUGGGGUUCCAUCACCAAGCACUCUGGAGCCGCAUCCGCGUCCACUGCUGCAGCGCGAGCUGAUGGUGCCGGGGACGCGGCACUCGGCCGUGCUCCGGGACCUGCGUUCCGGGACUCUGUACAGCCUGACACUGUAUGGGCUGCGAGGACCCCACAAGGCCGACAGCAUCCAGGGAACCGCCCGCACCCUCAGCCCAGUUCUGGAGAGCCCCCGUGACCUCCAAUUCAGUGAAAUCAGGGAGACCUCAGCCAAGGUCAACUGGAUGCCCCCACCAUCCCGGGCGGACAGCUUCAAAGUCUCCUACCAGCUGGCGGACGGAGGGGAGCCUCAGAGUGUGCAGGUGGAUGGCCAGGCCCGGACCCAGAAACUCCAGGGGCUGAUCCCAGGCGCUCGCUAUGAGGUGACCGUGGUCUCGGUCCGAGGCUUUGAGGAGAGUGAGCCUCUCACAGGCUUCCUCACCACGGUUCCUGACGGUCCCACACAGUUGCGUGCACUGAACUUGACCGAGGGAUUCGCCGUGCUGCACUGGAAGCCCCCCCAGAAUCCUGUGGACACCUAUGACGUCCAGGUCACAGCCCCUGGGGCCCCGCCUCUGCAGGCGGAGACCCCAGGCAGCGCGGUGGACUACCCCCUGCAUGACCUUGUCCUCCACACCAACUACACCGCCACAGUGCGUGGCCUGCGGGGCCCCAACCUCACUUCCCCAGCCAGCAUCACCUUCACCACAGGGCUAGAGGCCCCUCGGGACUUGGAGGCCAAGGAAGUGACCCCCCGCACCGCCCUGCUCACUUGGACUGAGCCCCCAGUCCGGCCCGCAGGCUACCUGCUCAGCUUCCACACCCCUGGUGGACAGAACCAGGAGAUCCUGCUCCCAGGAGGGAUCACAUCUCACCAGCUCCUUGGCCUCUUUCCCUCCACCUCCUACAAUGCACGGCUCCAGGCCAUGUGGGGCCAGAGCCUCCUGCCGCCCGUGUCCACCUCUUUCACCACGGGUGGGCUGCGGAUCCCCUUCCCCAGGGACUGCGGGGAGGAGAUGCAGAACGGAGCCGGUGCCUCCAGGACCAGCACCAUCUUCCUCAACGGCAACCGCGAGCGGCCCCUGAACGUGUUUUGCGACAUGGAGACUGAUGGGGGCGGCUGGCUGGUGUUCCAGCGCCGCAUGGAUGGACAGACAGACUUCUGGAGGGACUGGGAGGACUAUGCCCAUGGUUUUGGGAACAUCUCUGGAGAGUUCUGGCUGGGCAAUGAGGCCCUGCACAGCCUGACACAGGCAGGUGACUACUCCAUGCGCGUGGACCUGCGGGCUGGGGACGAGGCUGUGUUCGCCCAGUACGACUCCUUCCACGUAGACUCGGCUGCGGAGUACUACCGCCUCCACUUGGAGGGCUACCACGGCACCGCAGGGGACUCCAUGAGCUACCACAGCGGCAGUGUCUUCUCUGCCCGUGAUCGGGACCCCAACAGCUUGCUCAUCUCCUGCGCUGUCUCCUACCGAGGGGCCUGGUGGUACAGGAACUGCCACUACGCCAACCUCAACGGGCUCUACGGGAGCACAGUGGACCAUCAGGGAGUGAGCUGGUACCACUGGAAGGGCUUCGAGUUCUCGGUGCCCUUCACGGAAAUGAAGCUGAGACCAAGAAACUUUCGCUCCCCAGCGGGGGGAGGCUGAGCUGCUGCCCACCUCUCUCGCACCCCAGUAUGACUGCCGAGCACUGAGGGGUCGCCCCGAGAGAAGAGCCAGGGUCCUUCACCACCCAGCCGCUGGAGGAAGCCUUCUCUGCCAGCGAUCUCGCAGCACUGUGUUUACAGGGGGGAGGGGAGGGGUUCGUACAGGAGCAAUAAAGGAGAAACUGAGGUACCCGGCU